GAGCGGCUCUGACAGGACGGGUCGCAGGGGGUCGCCUGGCCGGAGCUGGGCUCCGAGAAUCCCGGGUGCCAGCACCAGAGCAGCGGCUCUCCGCACUAACUCUCCUCUCCUGGUCAGCUGUAACCCCUGCCGCAGAGCCCGGCAACUUUCAGCUGUCGCCCGCGGAGCCCCGAGGGCCACUCGCCUCACCUGUGCGUGCAGCGCCUCGCGCGCCCUGUCCGGCUGCGGAGAUGAGCGAGGUGAGCGGUGCGGCCCCCGGCGCUGUCGGCAGGGCUGCGGCGGGGAGGGUGCUGCGGCUCGGGAUCCCAGGGAGGCGAGGGAGAGCGAGGCAGACCGGAGCCGCGAAGAACCCUCCAGGGGCGCCCCACUGCCCUCCUAGGAAAGCUCCCACCUCGGGGCGCUGGGAAACGAUUGGAAGACGGGGUGCUUUCAGUCUCCCUACUGUGGACGGCGCUUUUGGGGGUAAUUGGAAUCGGCUGUAGAGUCCGGAAGCGGGGAUGCUGAGCUCUCAGGUGCUUAAUACCAAAACAUCCCCAGCAACCAACCAGGCAGCUGGCCAAGAGGAAAAAGGAAAAGCUGGCAAUGUCAAGAAGGCGGAGGAGGAGGAGGAGAUUGACAUUGAUCUGACAGCACCAGAAACAGAGAAGGCUGCCCUUGCUAUUCAGGGCAAGUUCCGGCGAUUUCAGAAAAGGAAAAAGGAUCCCAGCUCCUGAAUGGCCAGGCUUGCCCUUCACCUUCACCUUCAUGCUGGUCCCUUCUCUCCCCUUCUCCACACCCAUGUAUCUUUAUCCCUUGUCCCUCUAGCCUUUCCUUGAGGCAAGUUCAACCUUUAUAUACUCUUGUAUCUGGCCCCCUCAAGCCAUCACAGAAGUAGAGGCACAAGAGAGGUGGAGAAGAUGAAGACUUCAAUCAGCAGUCACUAGUCUAAGGGUGGAACAAUUUCUUCUUGGUAUAAGGUUCUUUGAUCAGUAGCUAUGCCUGCCCUGUAGGGCUAAACAAGAGGCUUCGAGGCUGAGAGAUCUCCCCAAAGAACAAUGUGGGAAGGAGGGGAAGGCUUUCAGAGUAGGGUGCCUGAGGGUGGGACAUAUGCACUGUUCUGCUAGUUACGGCAUUCACACUUUAGGUAACAUUUUUUUUCCCCUUCAGAUCCUUCUGCACCAACUCCAACUUCCCCUCCCAGGAUCUAAGCCACAGUGGGGACUGGAGCCUCGUUUUCCCCCUAGGCAGACCUAAAUCAAGCAGCUUACCACAAUAGUGCAUGCUGAGUAGAUUAGUUCCAAGGAAGGGAGACUGGAAUGCUGGUGUCAAGGAAAAGCCUCCCUCAUCAUCUAGUCUAAGACCAUAACGGGCAGAAGCAUAAGAGGUUCCAGGGCCAUAGGAGAAUGAGAAGUAGGGCACAUAUAGGGAGGAAAGAAAAGUGAAGAAGGGGGAAAUCUCUGAAUUUUUUUACUGCUGGGAAAAGUGUACUACAUGAAGGAUGCUUGGGGCUUUGCUAACCUGCUCACCGCUAACCCUCCAAGUCUAACCAUCCCCAGAGGCCACACAAACCAAGUGACUCCUGUAGUUCCCAUUUGCCCCACUAUGGAGUCAGGGCAAAAGUGGAAUAGCCACUCCAUGUGAUUUUAGCAUGUUUAAUCAUUUUAACAAUAAACCACCCCACAAAUGGGGUCAUUUAACCUCUA